AACGGUUCUACCCCGGCAGGGGUGCGGCUGCUCUCGAGGCUCAGCGCCCGAGGCCACGCCCCGCGCCCGCCCUGGGCCCGCCUCGUGCCCCUCGGAGCCGCCUCCCGCCCCGCCCCCCGCCCCUCGCCCCCCGCCCCUCGCCCCCCGCCGCCGCCACCGCGGUCAGCCAGCGGACCAGCGGCAGGAGCCGUUCCCCGACGGGCAGCAGGGCGCUCGGCCUCCGCGUGUGGGCUGAGCGCGGCGACGCUGCUGCCCCGAAAUCCCCGUGGAUUUUGAGUCGGUAAGUGGCUAGGGAGGAUGAGCGACACUGGGGGACGGAAGUCGGGCCCCGUGGUGUGGAGGAGGCGGGUGGGCGCCGUCUCCCAGGCCCGACCCCGGGAAAGUUGAGGCGAGGAAGAGAAGCUCUGAGUAUGGAACCUCAAAGUCUUUGUGACAAUGGAAACCAAAAAAUUAAUUGGUAAACCGCUUCAACCAGCAAGACCUGUUCGUCAUCUGACUUCUCCCCCAGGAGCAGUGUUCCCUUUCAACUUUCAAAACGAAUAUCCAUGCAACACUCAGUGCAUACAAAGUGGAGUUAGCAGAUGUAAGACGAAUGGAAUGCAAGCCUUUUCUCAAGGUCUUAAUGAGCAACAGCAACAGCAGUCUCCAGUUAAGAAAGAGAGAAUUAAAUACAGCAGAGAUUUCCUGUUGAAGCUCUCAAGUGUUUCCAUCUGCAGAAAAAAACCAGACUUUCUGCCUGAUCAUCCCAUUGUACUGCAAAAACCAGAAAACAACCAAAGUUUUAAGUAGCAUUUUAAGAACAGAUGAAUUUAAGUUUGGACAUCUGCAAAUGAGGUGGAUCUAGCAACAAUAACUGUAAUGGACUGUGACAAUUCAAUUUAUUCUUAAUUUUGAUGGUUGGCUAUUUGACUUCUCUAAAAAUGAGAAAGAGCUAUUUUAAAAUAUAAAGAAUUUUCUAAUCAGUUUCAGCUUUGCAGGAGGUUUCCUGCAUAAAUUGGGAAGUAACACUGGAAAGUAGGAAUUUGGUUAGUGAAGUGGGAAGACUGUAUAUUUAUAAUUUGCAUACUACUUGCAAUUUUUUGUUUUUCAUCACUUGUAAUAAUGGAAUGGAAAUGUAAGCUGUAAAGACUCUCAAAUAUAAAAUAUUUGCUACAGUGUAUAUAUGGUACAUAAUUGCUUGUUGCUUUUAAAGUUCCUUCUGUUGUUCUGCUUCCCACUGAUUUCAUACCAGCUCAUGAAUGGAUCAUUACAGUCUCUCCAGAGGCUUAGAAUGAUUCAGAAUGUUCAAUGCAUAGUUCUCAAUAAACAGGAGGCAGAAUUUUUAA